AGAGCUGCGGUUGGAGCCGAGCGCGCCGCGUCGCCCGCCGCCGGUGCAGAGCGUGGGGAGCACUCGGCCGCAGCCCUCGCCCGCCGCAGAGGGUCGCGUCCCGCGCCGCCGGCCAGGCCGCCCCGUGCCCAGGCCUUUCCAUCCUUGGAGCGGAUCGUUGCCCGCCUGACGCCCGCCCGCAGCGACAGCGCCCGCCGGAGCCGAGGCCGCGGCGGCGGCCGUGCCCAUGCCCGGGAACGGCUGUCUCCCCCUCCUCGCCUGUGUGACCUUGGCCAGCCAGCUUUUCCUGUGGCCGCCUGCGUUUUCUCACGGGUGAAAGCUCUGGCUUUAAGAUUCUGGAAUUUGGAAUGGCAGGUGUCCACGCUUAGCAGCUUUCUCACCGCCGCCAAACCUUGCCUGGGCACUGGGACCGUGGGUGGCCGCCUGUCCCUAGCUGUGGCUGAGCCAAGAUUGCACUUGUGAGAAGGCCUGACAGGCAGCAUGGGCGACAUGGCCAAUAGUUCCAUCGAGUUCCACCCCAAGCCCCAGCAGCAGCGGGAUGUCCCCCAGGCUGGAGGCUUUGGGUGCACGCUGGCGGAGCUGCGCACCCUCAUGGAGCUGCGAGGGGCCGAGGCGCUGCAGAAGAUCGAGGAGGCCUACGGGGAUGUCAGCGGGCUCUGCCGGAGGCUGAAGACCUCACCCACAGAGGGCCUGGCGGACAACACCAAUGACCUGGAGAAGCGCAGGCAGAUCUACGGGCAGAACUUCAUCCCCCCAAAGCAACCCAAGACCUUCCUGCAGCUGGUGUGGGAGGCCCUGCAGGACGUGACCCUCAUCAUCCUGGAGGUGGCUGCCAUCGUCUCUCUGGGCCUCUCGUUCUAUGCGCCGCCAGGAGAGGAGAGUGAAGCCUGUGGGAAUGUGUCGGGAGGCGCAGAAGAUGAGGGCGAGGCCGAAGCUGGCUGGAUCGAGGGGGCUGCCAUCCUGCUGUCCGUCAUCUGUGUGGUGCUGGUCACGGCCUUCAAUGACUGGAGCAAGGAGAAGCAGUUCCGAGGCCUGCAGAGCCGAAUUGAGCAGGAGCAGAAGUUCACGGUCAUCCGGAACGGGCAGCUCCUCCAGGUCCCCGUGGCUGCGCUGGUGGUGGGGGACAUUGCCCAGGUCAAGUACGGCGACCUGCUGCCAGCCGACGGCGUGCUCAUCCAGGCCAAUGACCUCAAGAUCGACGAGAGCUCCCUGACGGGCGAGUCUGACCACGUGCGCAAGUCAGCUGACAAAGAUCCCAUGCUGCUCUCAGGCACUCAUGUCAUGGAAGGUUCUGGAAGAAUGGUGGUGACCGCCGUUGGCGUGAAUUCCCAGACAGGCAUCAUCUUCACGCUGCUUGGAGCUGGCGGAGAGGAGGAAGAGAAGAAAGAUAAGAAAGGCAAGCAGCAGGAUGGGGCCAUGGAGAGUAGCCAGACCAAAGCUAAGAAGCAGGAUGGUGCAGUGGCCAUGGAGAUGCAGCCCCUGAAGAGCGCGGAGGGUGGGGAGAUGGAGGAGCGGGAGAAGAAGAAAGCCAACGCACCCAAAAAGGAGAAGUCUGUCCUUCAGGGGAAGCUCACAAAGCUAGCCGUGCAGAUCGGGAAAGCAGGGCUGGUGAUGUCUGCCAUCACCGUCAUCAUCCUGGUCCUCUACUUUGUGAUUGAGACGUUUGUCGUGGAAGGCCGGACAUGGCUGGCAGAGUGCACGCCGGUCUAUGUACAAUACUUCGUGAAGUUCUUCAUCAUUGGUGUCACUGUGCUGGUCGUGGCUGUCCCAGAGGGCCUGCCUCUUGCUGUCACCAUCUCCUUAGCUUACUCUGUCAAGAAAAUGAUGAAAGACAACAACCUGGUGCGCCACCUGGAUGCCUGCGAGACCAUGGGCAACGCCACAGCCAUCUGCUCCGACAAGACGGGCACGCUCACCACCAACCGUAUGACCGUGGUCCAGUCCUACCUAGGAGACACCCACUACAAAGAGAUUCCGGCCCCCAGCGCCCUGACCCCUAAGAUCCUCGACCUCCUGGUCCAUGCCAUCUCCAUCAACAGUGCCUAUACCACCAAAAUACUACCUCCUGAGAAGGAAGGCGCCCUCCCACGCCAGGUGGGCAAUAAGACGGAGUGCGCCCUGCUGGGCUUCGUCUUGGACCUGAAGCGGGACUUCCAGCCCGUGCGCGAGCAGAUCCCGGAAGACAAGCUUUACAAAGUGUACACCUUCAACUCGGUCCGCAAGUCCAUGAGCACAGUCAUCCGCAUGCCCGACGGUGGCUUCCGCCUCUUCAGCAAGGGGGCCUCAGAGAUCCUCUUGAAAAAGUGCACCAACAUCUUGAACAGCAAUGGCGAACUCCGGGGCUUUCGGCCUCGGGACCGGGACGACAUGGUGAGGAAGAUCAUCGAGCCGAUGGCUUGCGAUGGCCUCCGCACCAUCUGCAUCGCCUACCGGGACUUCUCUGCAGGCCAGGAGCCCGACUGGGACAACGAGAAUGAGGUCGUGGGUGACCUCACCUGCAUAGCUGUCGUGGGCAUUGAGGACCCUGUGCGGCCCGAGGUCCCUGAAGCUAUCCGAAAAUGCCAGCGUGCUGGCAUCACAGUCCGCAUGGUGACUGGGGACAACAUCAACACGGCCCGGGCCAUCGCAGCCAAAUGCGGCAUCAUCCAGCCCGGGGAGGACUUCCUGUGCCUAGAAGGGAAGGAGUUCAACCGGCGGAUCCGCAAUGAGAAAGGCGAGAUAGAACAGGAGCGGCUGGACAAGGUGUGGCCCAAGCUGAGGGUGCUGGCCCGGUCGUCUCCCACCGACAAGCACACACUGGUCAAAGGGAUUAUCGACAGCACCACUGGUGAGCAGCGGCAGGUGGUGGCUGUGACAGGGGAUGGCACCAACGAUGGGCCGGCCCUCAAGAAGGCGGACGUGGGCUUCGCCAUGGGCAUCGCAGGGACCGACGUGGCCAAGGAGGCCUCCGACAUCAUCCUGACCGAUGACAACUUCACCAGCAUCGUCAAGGCAGUCAUGUGGGGCCGUAACGUCUAUGACAGCAUCUCCAAGUUCCUGCAGUUUCAACUGACGGUCAAUGUGGUGGCUGUGAUCGUGGCCUUCACAGGUGCCUGCAUUACUCAGGACUCUCCUCUCAAAGCCGUGCAGAUGUUGUGGGUGAACUUGAUCAUGGACACAUUUGCCUCUCUGGCCCUGGCGACGGAGCCACCCACAGAGUCGCUGCUGCUGCGGAAGCCGUACGGCCGCGACAAGCCCCUCAUCUCCCGCACCAUGAUGAAGAACAUUCUGGGCCACGCCGUGUACCAGCUCGCCAUCAUCUUCACCCUGCUGUUUGUCGGGGAGCUCUUCUUCGACAUCGACAGCGGGAGGAAUGCGCCCCUGCACUCGCCACCCUCAGAGCACUACACCAUCAUCUUCAACACGUUCGUCAUGAUGCAGCUCUUUAACGAGAUCAACGCCCGCAAGAUCCACGGCGAGAGGAACGUGUUCGACGGCAUCUUCAGCAACCCCAUCUUCUGCACCAUCGUUUUGGGCACUUUCGGGAUUCAGAUUGUCAUCGUCCAGUUUGGCGGGAAGCCCUUCAGCUGCUCCCCACUAUCCACAGAACAGUGGCUCUGGUGCCUGUUUGUUGGUGUUGGGGAGCUGGUCUGGGGACAGGUCAUUGCCACCAUCCCCACCAGCCAGCUCAAGUGCCUGAAGGAAGCCGGGCACGGGCCCGGGAAGGACGAGAUGACCGACGAGGAGCUGGCCGAAGGCGAGGAAGAGAUCGACCAUGCCGAGCGGGAGCUCCGCAGGGGCCAGAUCCUCUGGUUCCGGGGCCUGAACCGGAUUCAGACGCAGAUGGAGGUAGUGAGUACCUUCAAGAGAAGCGGUUCAGUUCAGGGUGCUGUGCGCCGGCGGUCUUCGGUCCUCAGCCAGCUUCAUGACGUAACCAAUCUUUCUACCCCUACUCACGCAAUUCUCUCUGCUGCCAAUCCUACCAGUGCUGCUGGGAAUCCGGGUGGUGAAAGCGUUCCGUAGCUCGCUCUAUGAAGGCCUGGAGAAACCAGAAUCCAAGACCUCCAUUCACAACUUCAUGGCCACGCCCGAGUUUCUGAUCAAUGACUACACCCACAACAUCCCGCUCAUUGACGACACGGACGUGGACGAGAACGAGGAGCGCCUCCGGGCCCCCCCGCCCCCGUCCCCCAACCAGAACAACAACGCCAUAGACAGCGGCAUCUACCUGACCACGCAUGUCACCAAGUCAGCUACCUCUUCAGUGUUUUCCUCCAGUCCCGGGAGCCCGCUCCACAGCGUGGAGACGUCCCUCUAACAAGAACUUGUCUCAGCACAUGCGCACACGCACACUCGGACUCACACGAAGUCACACGCACACAUGCACGCACACACACAUAUGGGGACCUGCACACCUGCAAAACGAGGGAACAACUAAGGUGGCUGAAGACCUUUCUGGCAGGGCAUUUGCAAGGACCCAAAUCCAUUCAACAAGGGUGCAGCCUGCCACAGGCUCCUCAUCCGGACUGAGGAAGACGAGGACAGGGAGGAGGAAAAGGAGGAAGAGGAGGACAAAAAGGGGGAGGAGAAGGUUCUUCGUCCAAAGGAGGAAGGAGAAGAAGUAGAAAGUGCGAAGAGCUGAGUUCCCCACCUUUUUUUCUAUUGAUGCUUCUUUUUUAACAAACUACAGUUUUACCGUGUGUUUGCCAUUUGAGCUGUGUGGUGGGCAGGGGGCUGGUUUGGGUUUAUGGGGAGCUUUUGUUGCACCCAUGCAGGGGCAAUCAGAUCAGCAUCUUCAUGCAAAAAAAAAAAAAAAGUUGAGUGCUCUGCAGGCCUGUGAAGGGUGCCACCUGAGGGAGCCGCCUGCAAGCGGCCCUGCAGCCACAAAGCAACCCGCCCUCUGCAAAAACUAGGCACAUCCGCAGUGCGCAUGUGUGUGCGUGCAUGCACAUAUGUGUAUGUGUGUGGAUCUGUACACACACACGUAUAUAUGGCCAGAUGCGUAUUUCAAUAAGGAACUAUUUACUGGCAUGAUAUUUGCAUUCCUCUUAUCAGGCAUUUUCAUUUGGAAAUUUCAUUAUUGAAUGUAGCAAGGUUGUAGUUGUUUUUUUUUUUUUUUCAGGGAACUAGACUGCAAGAAUAUCUUUCUGGUCAACCCAUUUUUGUCCCUCAUCACCCCGCCCCCACCUUUCGCUCCUGCCCUCUGCCCGGCCCUACUGAGAUUCCCAAGGAGAAGGCCGAGAGGGGGCGCUCCAGGUCUGGAGCAGGUAUAAUUGGAGCAUUUGCACUGAGACCCCUGCCAGAGAGGAGAAAACCCUUUCAAGGGAAAUUUUAAUCUAAAAGGAAAAAACCAAAAUAUUGAUGAGAAGGAGUCCUCCAGUUAGUGAAAGGGGAGUUUCGUUUUCAGCUUUCUUUGGUUCCUACUCCAAUUCCACAUCCUUCAUCCUGGCCAUGCCCCCACCUUCAAGAGCAUGAAGCACUCUUGGAGUUGUGGGUCCUGCCCAGAGUCCAGAGAGCAGCCUCAGCUGAGCACAGGUCCGAGGGGGCGGGGGCAGGGCCAAGAGUUCAAAAGAAGCCAAUGGAGGGAGAGGGAGCGUCAGAAGCCCGGAGGAGCUGGUGGUGGGAGAAUGACGGCAGGGACGCAGCCACAGUUCAGACCCUGUCCCCUCAGCACCUGGAUGGACUCCCACUGUUUGCUUUGGCAAAUGCCGAGGAGUCCUCGGUAGACCACCUUGAUGUCUGCUGUGACAUCAGAGGUGCCACCACCAAAGCACUCUUCCCACCCUAGUCUUUGUGUCCAGCGGCCAAGCUUAAGCCAUGAAGUCAUGGAUUUGUGGCUCAGCACCAGGUCCUGAGGGGAGCGUAUCCUGGCAGUGUGGGCACCUGGUGGCCAAGCCUCAGUUUCCCCCAAAUGAGCAAAGGGGAUAAAGAGGGGCCCGACUUUUGCCACCCUCCUGAGGAAGCCCCUAGGUCCACACAGUGAUGCCAUGGGGGACCCUUGCCUUCCACACUUGCAGGUGUCACGUUUUGCAGGGAGGUGUUUGGGCCUUGGGCUCAGCCACUGGGAGACAGUUGGGACCUGAGGGACAGAGGAUCGGAAUGGAAACCACCAACGUGCACUGGCACCCUCAGAAGGCUUGUCUCACCUCCACCGGCAUCCACACAAAACCAAACAGGAGCAGGCGUCAUCCCCACUAUUCCCAUGAAUGCCAUGUCACCCCUGAGCAGAAGCAGUCAAAUCUUGGGCAAAAGAAUUUCGGUUAGAAAAGAAAAUCCCACUUUAAAAUGCCAGCUGCAGAUAACUCAAAGCCAUCCCUUUUUUCUAAAGGGCACAUUGAGAAUGUCACCCAUUUGUAAACUGUUCCCUGAUGUCCUUGUUUAAACGAUAAUAAGAAAAAGGGCAACUCCAUUUGUUGAGGGUCUUUGUGUUCUUCAAUGAGAAAUCAAAUUUGAGACGUUGAAAUUGGAGCUGCGUGCUGCUGCACUCACCGGCUUCUUCUCACUCUCUGUCGUAGACACACCGAUAGGACCAAUGGCCAAUAGAUAUUAAAAGCAAACCCUCACUGCUGCUGUAUAAAGUUGCCUAAUGUAAAUGUCUAUUGUUUAGUCCCUAGGUCACCUUUGUGCUGUGCUGUGGAGUUCAGAAACGGGGUACCAUGACCUGGAAUCUUUUGCUCUUGUUUUUGCAGUCUUCAAGGCUGGGGGCCCUGUCUCAUUGGGAAGCCCCUCUUUAUAAAGCAUUAUAUUACUUGGAAUGGCUUGGUCAACUGUGUUCAGUUCAUAAAUAUGUUUUACAUUUUUAUCUGCCUGUUAUAAAGAUGAACAAAAAAACUUAAUGAGAAAGAUCACAGAUACGUAAUAAUUUAAAGUCUGUAGUUGAAUUUCCUAACUUAAAGAAUAGACCAAAAUUUCUGUGUAUAAAAAAAAAUGAAAGGCUCCUUACAUCCUG